AAGCAAACCCUGGGAACCCUUCAAUCACCUGCAGCACAGAGUCCUUUCUCCAUGUUAUGUGGGGCCAUCCUGGCGUCCCAGCCCCUGUGAAUGAGGCCUCAACACCAGCUCAGCCAGUCCUGGAAGCCAUCUGAGAGCUGCUCUACCGCUCAAGCCAAUGUGUUAAAUACGGCAUUUUGGAUACGUCGUCACCAGUGAGCCAAGCUGAAUGCUAGUUAAAGCGGGAGAUGGUCGAUGAAUACGUGCAGGAAGAAAUGGACAGGACAAUCCAGAGAGAUCGCGUGUUCUGAGGACAGCACAGCCAGGCUCCGAUGCCAGCAAUGAGGACACUCCCCCUCCCGGAUGCAGGACUGGUUGCCACCAUGGGGAGGGGUGCACCGUGCCACGUGCUCCCAGGACACUGGCCAGGGGGCUAUAAAGAACAUCUCGAGAGGAGCCAGCACAGCCUUGUUCAGACGCCCAGUGACCUGCCGAGGUCGGCAGCACAGAGCUCUGGAGAUGAAGACCCUGUUCCUGGGUGUCACGCUCGGCCUGGCCGCUGCCCUGUCCUUCACCCUGGAGGAGGAGGAUAUCACAGGGACCUGGUACGUGAAGGCCAUGGUGGUCGAUAAGGACUUUCCGGAGGACAGGAGGCCCAGGAAGGUGUCCCCAGUGAAGGUGACAGCCCUGGGCGGUGGGAAGUUGGAAGCCACGUUCACCUUCAUGAGGGAGGAUAGGUGCAUCCAGAAGAAAAUCCUGAUGCGGAAGACGGAGGAGCCUGGCAAAUACAGCGCCUAUGGGGGCAGGAAGCUCAUGUACCUGCAGGAGCUGCCCAGGAGGGACCACUACAUCUUUUACUGCAAAGACCAGCACCAUGGGGGCCUGCUCCACAUGGGAAAGCUUGUGGGUAGGAAUUCUGAUACCAACCGGGAGGCCCUGGAAGAAUUUAAGAAAUUGGUGCAGCGCAAGGGACUCUCGGAGGAGGACAUUUUCACGCCCCUGCAGACGGGAAGCUGCGUUCCCGAACACUAGGCGAGGCCUCCCUCCGGCUCCCUCAGGUGUCAGCUCAGCCCAUCGCCCCCUGCACCUGUCCCCACGCGGUCCACUCCCCACCAUCCACCCACCAAGGAUGCUCAGAGGCCUGCCCAGUCAUUGGAGGAGCUGAGGUCGCUCUGGAGCCCCGAGGUUGCCCAGCAGUGGCCGAUGUGGGGGCUGCAGAGCCUGGGGAGGGAGCUCUGGCCCUGGCCUCUGCCCUACCCUGCAGCCUCCCUGACCUCUGCUCCUCUUCCCAGCACAGCAGCCCCCGGGUCUGCACCUCCAGAGCCCACCCUACCACCAGACACAGAGCCUGGACCACCUGGACCUACCCUCCAGCCAUGACCCUUCCCUGCUCCCACCCACCUGACUCCAAAUAAAGUCCUUCUCCCCCA